CUCGCUUUUCUUGCAAUAUUUUAUACCUUUUCAAUUCAUAGAAUUACUCAAGAAAACUACCUCAGUUGGUUGCUACUUUUUGUUGAUUCCUUUUACCAGACAUGACUAAGUUUCUUUUUCAUCAGUAGAUUUCUGGGCUCCUAUAUUCACUAGAGAUUGCAACUCCUGGAUUUCUCUUACACUAGAAUCCUAUUUCGAGCCAUAUGGGAGAUUCUGAAUUCCAGAACAAAAGAAUUUUGUAAUUUAAAAUUCGUGAUUGCUCAAUGGAAUCAUUUUAAUUGUUACUUCAUUUCUGUCGUUAUUUAAAACUUAAGUGGAGAGUUUUCUCAGGGAUAAGAAAACCACAAUCAAGGUCAUACAAAACUUUUAGAGGCAGUCAGUCUGCUAAGAAGGCUCCAGCAAGAGAAACGGGAUCUUCUGUUUCAACAAUCAUUACUUAAGAAAAAAUUAAGAAAAUGAAAUAAGUUUUGCAGAAUAACUGUGAAAUUUUUAUUCAUGAAAUAUGUACUUACACUUUGGGCCACGUGAUGUCACUCUUUGCCGCGAUGUUCUCUCUGAAUCCAGACAAAUACAGCCCUUUUCCCAUGGGAAAGAGGCUCAAUUCUUUUUCACUCUCUCUGUGCUGAACGAUGGCGAACACAGCAGAAUGGGACUGACGAAAUCAGAUGAUUUCUUCUAAUUUGGAGGCAAUUUUCACUAAUUAGAAGAAGACUGAGUAUUUGAAAUGUUAUACUCAAGUCGAGGAGAUCCAGAGGGUCAGCCUCUACUGCUCUCGCUUCUGAUCCUCGCAAUGUGGGUGGUGGGGAGCGGCCAGCUCCACUACUCCGUCCCGGAGGAAGCCGAACACGGCACCUUCGUGGGCCGCAUCGCGCAGGACCUGGGGCUGGAGCUGGCGGAGCUGGUGCCGCGCCUGUUCCAGUUGGAUUCCAAAGGCCGCGGGGACCUUCUGGAGGUAAAUCUGCAGAAUGGCAUUUUGUUUGUGAAUUCUCGGAUCGACCGCGAGGAGCUGUGCGGGCGGAGCGCGGAGUGCAGCAUCCACCUGGAGGUGAUCGUAGACAGGCCGCUGCAGGUUUUCCAUGUGGACGUGGAGGUGAAGGACAUUAACGACAACCCUCCAGUGUUCCCAGCGACACAAAAGAAUCUGUUCAUCGCGGAAUCCAGGCCGCUUGACUCUCGGUUUCCACUAGAGGGCGCGUCCGAUGCAGAUAUCGGGGAGAACGCCCUGCUCACUUACAGACUGAGCCCCAAUGAGUAUUUCUUCCUGGACGUGCCAACCAGCAACCAGCAGGUAAAACCUCUUGGACUUGUAUUACGGAAACUUUUAGACAGAGAAGAAACUCCGGAGCUUCAUUUAUUGCUCACGGCCACCGAUGGAGGCAAACCCGAGCUGACUGGCACCGUUCAAUUACUCAUCACGGUACUGGACAACAAUGACAAUGCCCCAGUGUUCGACAGAACCCUGUAUACGGUGAAAUUACCAGAAAACGUUUCUAUCGGAACGCUGGUGAUUCACCCCAAUGCCUCAGAUUUAGACGAAGGCUUGAAUGGGGAUAUUAUUUACUCCUUCUCCAGUGAUGUUUCUCCAGAUAUAAAAUCCAAGUUCCACAUGGACCCCUUAAGUGGGGCAAUCACAGUGAUAGGACAUAUGGAUUUUGAAGAAAGUAGAGCACACAAGAUCCCAGUCGAGGCUGUCGAUAAAGGCUUCCCACCCCUGGCUGGUCAUUGUACACUUCUUGUGGAAGUUGUGGAUGUAAAUGACAAUGCUCCACAGUUGACUAUCAAAACGCUCUCGGUUCCUGUAAAAGAGGACGCACAACUGGGGACAGUUAUUGCCCUGAUUAGUGUGAUCGACCUAGACGCAGAUGCCAACGGGCAGGUUACCUGCUCCCUGACGCCCCACGUCCCCUUCAAGCUGGUGUCCACCUACAAGAAUUACUACUCGUUGGUGCUGGACAGAGCUCUGGACCGCGAGAGUGUGUCCGCCUACGAGCUGGUGGUUACCGCGCGGGACGGGGGCUCGCCUUCACUGUGGGCCACGGCCAGGGUGUCUGUGGAGGUGGCCGACGUGAACGACAACGCACCAGCGUUCGCGCAGUCCGAGUACACGGUGUUCGUGAAGGAGAACAACCCGCCGGGCUGCCACAUCUUCACGGUGUCUGCGCGGGACGCUGACGCGCAGGAGAACGCCCUGGUGUCCUACUCGCUGGUGGAGCGGCGGUUGGGCGAGCGCUCGCUGUCGAGCUACGUGUCAGUGCACGCGGAGAGCGGCAAGGUGUACGCGCUGCAGCCGUUGGACCACGAGGAGCUGGAGCUGCUACAGUUCCAGGUGAGCGCGCGCGACGCGGGCGUGCCGCCUCUGGGCAGCAACGUGACGCUGCAGGUGUUCGUGCUGGACGAGAACGACAAUGCGCCGGCGCUGCUGACACCUCGGAUGAGGGGCACUGACGGCGCAGUGAGCGAGAUGGUGCUGCGGUCGGUGGGCGCCGGCGUAGUGGUGGGGAAGGUGCGCGCAGUGGACGCCGACUCGGGCUACAACGCGUGGCUUUCAUACGAGCUGCAGCCAGAAACGGCCAGCGCGAGCAUCCCGUUCCGCGUGGGGCUGUACACGGGCGAGAUCAGCACAACGCGUGCCCUGGACGAAACGGACGCACCGCGCCAGCGCCUACUGGUGCUGGUGAAAGACCACGGGGAGCCAGCGCUGACGGCCACGGCCACUGUGCUGGUGUCGCUGGUGGAGAGCGGCCAGGCGCCAAAGUCAUCGUCGCGGGCGUCAGUGGGUGCCACGGGCCCCGAGGUGACGCUGGUGGAUGUCAACGUGUACCUGAUCAUCGCCAUCUGCGCGGUGUCUAGCCUGUUGGUUCUCACGCUGCUGCUGUACACUGUGCUGCGGUGCUCGGCGAUGCCCACCGAGGGCGAGUGCGCGCCUGGCAAGCCGACGCUGGUGUGUUCUAGCGCGGUGGGGAGUUGGUCGUACUCGCAGCAGAGGAGGCAGAGGGUGUGCUCUGGCGAGGGUAAGCAGAAGACCGACCUCAUGGCCUUCAGCCCGGGCCUUUCUCCUUGUGCUGGAUCUACAGAGCGAACGGGAGAACCCUCUGCUUCCUCAGAUUCAACUGGGAAGGUGGGUUUUUCUAGCAUUUUAUUUAUUUAUAUAAUUUUUUUUCUUGAAAGAUAUUAUCGAUUACUCCCAGGGGCCGUUCAAAUAGUUUUAUUCAUUUUUCUAGAAAUCCAGCAGAUUUUUUUUCUGAUAAAGUAAACCCCUUAACAUUGGAGCCGACUUUGUCUUGACUUCUAGUGAGAAUUAUAAACUGUAUAUUAAAUAGAUAUUUUUUGGGUGCUGAAUCAAUUUUAUUUAAAUUUGUGAUUAAAGUGACAUUGAAUUUCUGAUGCUAUGCUGCCAUAACACUUGAAAACCAAUUUAGUUGUUAGUCAUUCAUUAAACAUUAACAUCACUAUCAUUUAUUUAUUGCUAAAUGAUGCAUAGUAUUUUAGUCUACUUGUAUUGUUUAUAAGAAACCCAAGCAAAAAUAUAUAGCAAUUGUUACCUUGUUAAGUUUGUAGUUCUCUACAUUUCUCUGGAUGGAGACUGUGAACAUCUGAUUGUUCAGCAACCUUCAGUAUCUAUUAUUUUAAUAAGAAAGAAACUUCCCCUAAACUUUAGAAAACAGUUGCUCCACUUUAGGAAUCAAAUUAUGUCAAUAAAUGUUAUAAACACAGCCUUCAUUUCAACUUAUAUAAAAUAUGUUUUAAAAUGCCUGACAAUGUAGAUAAUUCAAGAAAUGUUGACUGAAAUUUUGUCUACACUUAGAACAUUUUUUGAAAUUCAGUUUACAGAAAUUGGAGAAAAUGCUUUUUAAACAAGUGUUUCCUUUCUUCAAGAAGACAUUCUCCUUUUAAUUGAAAUUUUCUCCAUUCAGUGAUAAAAUGAUCAGCCAUGUGAAGAUUCGAAACUUCGAGUUCUUUUGAAAUUCAGAGUCUGUAACUUAAAACAUUACCCUUAUGAAUUUAGAUGAGAAUUCACUUGUUCUGUCAGUAAUCCAUAAGACAGAAAUCUGUUUUUUUAAAAAUAUCUUUUUCUCCUCUCAGCUCAUACAUAACACAAGGCAGAAAUCUGGAUAUGAGAUUUGCCUCUUUAAUGUCACUACAUGUUAUGUUUCCUGAAUUGUAGUAUGUGACUUUCAAAAUGGUGGUUUUCCACACUCUACCUUUAGUGCAAGCUAUUUGUUUGUUUUCUAAUUUAUAGUUUUAAAAACUUCGCUUAUUGAGUUUUUGUUAUGUGGUUUAUAUUUUUCUUUCUCUUUCAGCUAUUUUAUUUAAUAUUGUGUCAGAUAUUUUACAAGGUAUGACCUAAUUAAAAACUCAGUAGAGAAAGAUCAGAAUGGCCUUGAGAAUAGAGCCACAAAAAUAACUAUGAAAAUGCCAGUAACGUUUAUUUAAAACAAAAUAUUUUAAUUUUUAAAUUUUCCCUUAAAACACACUUUUGGAAUAUGCUACAAUAUUACAUGUUUUUUGUCUUUUUAUUUUUCUGAGACGGAGUCGUUUUCUGCCACCCAGGCUGGAGUACAGUGGCAUGAUCUUGGCUCACUGCAACGUCUGCCUCCUGGGUUCAAGCAAUUCUCCUGCCUCAGCCUCCUGAGUAGCUGGGAUUAUAGGCACAUGCCACCGCGCCCAGCUAAUUUUUGUAUUUUUAGUAGAGAUGGGGUUUCAUCAUGUUGGCCAGGUUGGUCUCGAACUCCUGACCUUGUGAUGCUCCCACCUCGGCCUCCCAAAGUGCUGGGAUUAAAGCUGUGAGCCACUGUGCCAAGGCUUUUUUAUUUUUUUUUUUUGUCAUUUUCUUUCAAAACUUGAGUGGUCUCUGAGCUCCUGUCAUUAAACCUAUCUAUAUCUGUCUAUCAGCACAACUCACCUUGAAUAUAGUCUUAUACUUUCAAGUAUCUUUGUCUUUGCACGUUUUUCAAGUUUCAUGUGCCAUUUAAACUUGGACCCAGGUAUCUGAUUAUUUGAUGUGAAUAGAGGGAUGCUACAGAUGUCAUUUGUCUCCCGCCCUAAGUCCUCCAGUCUCCUUAGAGCUAGUACUUACUAAGCAUUUACUAUGUCAUCAAUAAUCAUAAAACGUAUUUUUUUUUUUGAGUCAGAGUCUCGCUCUGUUGCCCAGGCUGGAGUGCAGUGGUGCCAUCUUGGCUCACUCCAAGCUCCCCCUCCCGUGUUCACGCCAUUCUCCUGCCUCAGCCUCCCGAGUAGCUGGGACUACAGGCGCCUGCCACCAUGCCCGCCUAAUUUUUUUGUAUUUUUAGUAGAGAUGGGGUUUCACCGUGUUAGUCAGGAUGGUCUCGAUCUCCUGACCUCAUGAUCCUCCCGCCUCAGCCUCCCAAAAUGCUGGGAUUACAGGCGUGAGCCACCGCGCCUGGCCUAAAAUGUGUUCUUUAUUAUUGACGGCUGUAUUGAUGGGAUUGGUAAUUUAGUCCUUCAUAUUAAUCUCUAUUCUCUCUCAGAGUACAAGCUCUCAUCAUAUGCAAAUUCUCAGAAGGGCUGUGAACACCUUAGUAAUAAAUUUAUCUUUUGAGGUCAUUAGCAAACAUGAACUCACAGGGAUCCAGAGAUGGUAAAAUUCAAAACAGCCUGUCAAGUUCAAAACAGAGAGGUGAAAGCAGAAGAGACACUUUCCUAUUUUGCCUAAUAGGUCUCCUUAUAUGCAUCUGUAGUUAACAUUCCUCAAUUCAAGUUAGAAUCAUGAAACAAUAAUGAAGCUCCUCCUAUGUCUCUUUUCAAGUUGUAAUUACUAUAUAGGAAAAACUAAGUUGUCACCCAAUAUCUUAGACACUUUGAGAGCAAAGGGGGUGCUGUAAAUAAGUAUACAAGAUCACAGACCUAAAUUGAGCCUGUUCCAGACAAAUUGGGGCCUAUGGUCAACCUAUCCUUAGACCUGCUAACGCAUUAGCAUUAGCAGCACCUAAGUCCUCAUUGAAUGUUCUGGUUCAAGGCUCCACCUCAGAAAUUCUGAAAUGGGUAGUAAGAGCAAAUUUUCAUUUUAAAGCACACCUGAGAUGAUUCUCAUACAACCGAAAUUUUAGAUCCAUAGCCCUAUUUGAUACUUGACAGUGCAAGUUUCUGUAAUUUAAAAAGAUGUGGUGGCCUGACACCUGCAAUCCCAACAUUUUGGGAGGCCAAGGUGGGAGGGUCCCUUCCUUGAGCCCAGCAGUUUGAGACCAAUGUAGUGAGACUCAUCUCUGCCAAAAAAAAAAAAUUAGCCGGGCAUGGUGGCACACAUCUCUAGUCCCAAUUACUCAGGAGGCUGAGGCGAGAGAAUCGCUUGAGCCUGGGACAUUGAGGCUGCAGUGAACUGUGAUGGCACAACUGCAUUUCAGCCCGGGUGACAGCAAGAUUCUGUCUC